AGUUUGCCCAAAGCUUGCUGGCCGCUGUGUAGGGCUGGUGAGUGGCUGGGGCUGUCUGAGCCAUGAACAACUUCAGGGCCACCAUCCUCUUCUGGGCAGCGGCAGCAUGGGCUAAAUCAGGCAAGCCUUCGGGAGAGAUGGACGAAGUUGGAGUUCAAAAAUGCAAGAAUGCCUUGAAACUACCUGUCCUGGAAGUCCUACCUGGAGGGGGCUGGGACAAUCUGCGGAAUGUGGACAUGGGACGAGUUAUGGAAUUGACUUACUCCAACUGCAGGACAACAGAGGAUGGACAGUAUAUCAUCCCUGAUGAAAUCUUCACCAUUCCCCAGAAACAGAGCAACCUGGAGAUGAACUCAGAAAUCCUGGAAUCCUGGGCAAAUUACCAGAGUAGCACCUCCUACUCCAUCAACACAGAACUCUCUCUUUUUUCCAAAGUCAAUGGCAAGUUUUCCACUGAGUUCCAGAGGAUGAAGACCCUCCAAGUGAAGGACCAAGCUAUAACUACCCGAGUUCAGGUAAGAAACCUCGUCUACACAGUCAAAAUCAACCCAACUUUAGAGCUAAGCUCAGGUUUUAGGAAGGAACUCCUUGACAUCUCUGACCGUCUAGAGAACAACCAGACGAGGAUGGCCACCUACCUGGCAGAACUCCUGGUGCUCAACUAUGGCACCCACGUCACCACCAGUGUCGACGCUGGGGCUGCUCUUAUUCAGGAGGACCACCUCAGGGCCUCCUUCCUCCAAGACAGCCAGAGCAGUCGUAGUGCCGUGACCGCCUCUGCUGGACUUGCCUUUCAAAACACCGUGAACUUCAAAUUUGAGGAAAACUAUACCUCGCAGAAUGUCCUCACCAAGAGCUACCUCUCAAACCGAACCAACUCCAGGGUGCAGAGCAUUGGAGGGGUUCCUUUUUACCCAGGCAUCACCCUCCAGGCCUGGCAGCAGGGUAUCACCAACCACCUGGUGGCCAUCGACCGCUCUGGCCUGCCGCUGCAUUUCUUCAUCAACCCCAACAUGCUACCUGACUUGCCAGGCCCCCUGGUGAAGAAGGUGUCAAAGACAGUGGAAACUGCUGUGAAGCGCUAUUAUACAUUCAACACCUACCCUGGCUGCACAGAUCUCAAUUCUCCCAACUUCAAUUUUCAGGCCAACACGGAUGAUGGCUCCUGCGAGGGGAAAAUGACCAACUUCUCUUUCGGUGGGGUUUAUCAGGAAUGCACUCAGCUCUCAGGGAAUAGGGAUGUCCUCCUCUGCCAAAAGUUGGAGCAGAAGAAUCCACUCACUGGUGAUUUCUCCUGCCCCUCUGGCUACUCCCCGGUGCACCUGUUAUCCCAGAUCCACGAGGAGGGUUACAACCACCUGGAGUGUCAUCGAAAGUGCACUCUCCUCGUCUUCUGCAAGACCGUGUGUGAAGAUGUGUUCCAGGUGGCAAAAGCUGAAUUUAGGGCUUUUUGGUGUGUGGCCAGCAGCCAAGUACCUGAAAACUCAGGACUGCUUUUUGGGGGCCUCUUCAGCAGCAAGAGCAUAAACCCCAUGACAAAUGCACAGUCAUGCCCAGCCGGCUACUUUCCACUGAGACUCUUUGAAAACCUCAAGGUAUGUGUUUCUCAGGACUAUGAGUUGGGAAGCAGGUUUGCGGUCCCCUUUGGCGGGUUCUUUAGCUGCACAGUUGGGAACCCCCUGGUAGAUCCUGCUAUAUCCAGAGAUUUAGGGGCACCGUCUCUGAAAAAGUGCCCCGGGGGCUUCAGCCAGCACCCAGCCCUCAUCAGCGAUGGAUGCCAAGUGUCCUAUUGCGUCAAAUCCGGGCUCUUCACAGGAGGGUCCCUGCCCCCUGCCAGGCUCCCACCUUUCACCCGGCCACCCCUCAUGAGUCAGGCUGCCACCAAUACUGUCAUAGUGACCAAUUCUGAGAAUGCGAGAUCCUGGAUUAAAGACUCCCAGACCCACCAGUGGAGGCUGGGAGAACCGAUAGAGCUGCGGAGGGCCAUGAAUGUCAUCCAUGGGGAUGGUGGUGGUCUGUCAGGAGGGGCUGCAGCUGGGGUCACAGUGGGGGUCACCACCAUUCUGGCUGUUGUUAUCACCUUGGCCAUCUACGGCACCCGGAAGUUCAAGAAGAAAGCAUAUCAGGCAAUUGAGGAAAGGCAGAGUUUGGUUCCAGGCACUGCAGCAACUGGAGACACCACUUACCAAGAGCAGGGGCAGAGUCCAGCUUAAAUCUCUCCCCGAAAAUGGUUUCUCUCAUCUCCAGUGUGGUCAUUGCUGACCACUCUGUUUUCCUAAGCAUUGAAAUGGCAAGUGCAACCAAAAGUAGGUAUAUUCGUGACUUCUUGUUUAGGUCUCUGGGCCAGGAAAUUCAUACUGUUACAUGGAUAAGGUUGGGAUUGGGGAGAGGGAACAGUUGGGACUAGAAGCAAAAGUGAUUCUGGGACUAAAAUAGGAAGCAGAUGUCCUUUCCCAAUGUGUGUUGCUGUCUUCACCUGAAUGCAUUUGUGUAAAAAUAGCGGAGGGACAAUGUGAACAUUUGUAUUUGGAAGCUAUGAAUUUACUCUGAAGUUUGCAGUUGUUUCCAAUUUGUGAGCUCUAAGAGUUUCUGCCUGUAAGAACUACUCUCCUUUUAUUUUGAUUUUUAAAAACCUGUCUGAAUUUCACACUCUUAGAGCCUGGAAGAGCCCUGAAAAGACACAAGUCUUGCCUGGCUACUGCUUUUUAACUUUGAGGGCUCUAUGUUGACAGACUGUUAUCUCCUCUGGGUGACCUCAAACAUCUGAAAAGAAAGAUGUUGCCUGUGCCAAUUCCACUUUUUCCAGCUGCCCCUUGAUGAACACUCCCUUAUACCAGACCACUCUUGGACUUCUGACUGGUGUCAUCAAGUCCUCAGAAAAUAUUUUAAGUUAUUUUAAGUUAUUAAGGAAGGGAUGAUUUGGAGACAAGGAGUAAUGAAAGAUGGGUAAAAACUGGAAAAGAUUCUGGUGCUAAGUACUACCCCUUCAUCUUCCAUGGAUGGUCAUUACCUUUCCUGUCCUCCUGUUAUAUGAACACACACACACACACACACACACACACACACACACACGCACACACAUACCACAUUUCAAUAAGUCUUCAUUGUUCUGGGUCCUUACCUUUCCUGUCCUCCUGUUAUAUGAACACACACACACACACACACACACACACACACGCACACCACAUUUCAAUGUCUGCAUGGUUCUGGGGGUAACAAAGGCAAGAAGUUAAAGUAAGACCACAUUUGAGUAUUACUUACUCUGUAGAAUCAAAACAGAGUAGUUAACACCAAUUAUGCAAACUACUUUUUUUUCCAGCAGAAAGGGAGCUGACAUGAUCAAAUCCAUGUUUUCAAAUGAACUGAAAAAGGCAUCCAGCACCACUUAUAACACAUUUAUUUCAGUUCCAGGCUGACAGCCCUGGGGCAUCUAGCAGGAUGCAUAAUUGUCAUCUGGUGAGAGUUGGGACUUUGCUCAAUUUUAAUACCAAUCUCUCCUGAUUGUAAUUACCUCCACUACUUUCAUGAUCCCCCUACAAUAUUUUUUUAAAUGAUAUAUUUAUUCACUGAAUCAAAUGUCAUUAAUGAGUUAUCUUCUGUGGAGGAUGACUGUUCUCUUUGUUAAUGUUCACAAUCAAGAUCUUGGGCUGAGAAGAGGCCCUUCACCCAAGGAGUUUGAAGUAUCACAGUGUGUGGGAAGGUGGGAACCAGGAUACCCAUUCAUUUCCAACCGAGACACAGAGAAGUGAGUCACAGAAUUUGAGCCCGCUCUCUUGACUGCCCAGCCAGAGACACUGAUUUCUGUAACCUCUUCACUUGAUCCUGCCUCUUAAGCAUUAAAACAUUCUCCUAAACCUCUGAGUGUUUUGUGGGUUCUGGGUGUUUUGUACAUUUUAGCCAAGCUAACCACUUGUCUGCAAGUACUGACUUUCCUAUGAAUUCUUUGAAGAUUAUUGAGUCAGAAAGGAAAAAUAUAGCCCCAAAUUCCCAGGCUUUUAAUGCAUUACAUUAACUGCCUAUUGAAAUGAGAAGUUCUUCACAAACUUGUAUACCCACUAACAAGAUUGCACAUAAACAUGCAUUAAAGUAUAUACUAAGAAACCCUCUGUCCAACGGCUCAUGCAUAUGAAGUCCGAACAUGGGAGUUUGCCAAUUGCAUUCAUCAAGUCGUUUUGCGGAGUCAGAUCCCUGAUGGAAGAGCUCACAGGCUCUGCCUUCCAAGUCCUGGGUUCCUAACUGGUGACCUUAGCCUGGGGUCUGUGGGGAGACCAACCCUGGCUUCCAAGAAAACCACAUUCCAUGGACUAUCAGAAAUAGACACAGAUUUGGGUGACAAAGCUGGCUCUGUAUUUGCAUUUUAUUUUUGUGUUCUUGUCAGUUUGGGAAUGAUUAAUAUUAAACAUUUAUUUGAGAAACAA